CAAAAUGAUACCAGGCAUCAUAUAAAUGGGAAUCUGGAAGACGGGAAAACUCGCUGUGGGUUUGAAUGAGUCAAUAUACAGAAUUUAGGAACUGUGUUGAGGCUUAUGUGAAGUGUUCAUAUAAGGGAACACUUGGAAAACAAAAGUUGAAAAGUUAGGUUAGGGGCCAGAAUGUUGGAGAUCUUGCCUUUCUUCCUCUACUGUCCUUCCCCCAACUCCACCCCCUCAAUAAACUAAGGAUAAAAUGAUAGGCUAAACUGAGGUAGUAGUAGUAGAAAUGGAAAGCAAAUUAGACUCACUGAGAAGUUUGUGAACAGGUGGUGAGAUAACCUAGUAUAAAGUUGUUAUUAAAUAUUAGAGUGUAAUGUAUAAUAAAAGUUUGGGUCUUUAAAUGCAAAUUAAAAUAAUGAAACACUUGAUUCUUGACAGUGCUUUCAUCUCCUUGAAACCCAUAUCCUUCCACAUUACUGUCUUAUAAGCAUAAUCCCUGGAUUGCUAGUAUCAACCUAAAUUUCAGCUGCCUUAUUGUGUGAAUUGCUUUUAUAUCAGUUGGUGUCACCAUUAUUCAUCCAUACAGUCAUCUAAUUCAGAAUUCUGUGAGGAACCCUAGACUUUCCUCACUAUUUUACCCUGAUAUUCCAUUAGUCACUCAAUUCUGUUUAGUCUGCUAACUAGCUGUCAAUAUAAUUCCUUUUCUUUAAUCCAUACUGCUUAAUUAACCCAAAUCUUCUCUUUCCUACAUAAUAUAGUAGCCUACUAAUAGCUCAUAUUUCCCCAGCCUCCCCCACCCCACUCUACUUUCUAAUGGAUGUCAGAAAUAUUUUCUUAAAAGACAAAUAUAAUUAUUUUACUAUUGCCCAUUGUUUAUAUAAUAUCAAAGCUCUUUACUCUGACAUUCAUGAUGUGACUCUUGCCUAUGUCUCUAGCCUUAUUCCCUGAGAAAGUUUCAGGAAUCAUGUAGAACAACAUAGUUCCCUCGAUGUGUCAUGUCUUUGUAUUUUAUAUUUCUUUUUACUGGUAUUGUUGUAUCCACAUAGACUUAACUAUCCUUUUCUACGUAUCCUGACAAAUUUCUGCUCCUUCCCAAGAUUUAUCUCAUCUGGAAGGCUGUUUUAGUCCAUACUCUUGCAGGCAGAGUGAGGCUUUCCUGUUUUGGUUACUCCCGUUAUAGCUCCUAACAUACAUUGUAAUUGUGCAUCCAUACUUAUUUACCUGGCAUUUCCUUGAAGUCAGCACUUGUGCUUCAUUUAUCUUUGUAUUUUCAAGUACUUAGUUCAAGACUUUCCAGAAAAUGAGCUUGUCUUAGUCCAUGCAGGCUGCUAUAACAAAAACCAAAGACUGGGUGGCAGAAACAAUGAAUAUUUAUUUCUCACAGUUCCGCAAGCUGAGAAGUCCUAGAUCAGGGUGCCAGCAAAUUGUGUCUAAUGAAUGUCUGCUUCCUAGUUCAUAAACAGCUAUCUUUGCACUGUGUCCUCAACAGGGCAGAAGAGGGCCAGGGAGCUCUUGGGGUCUCUUUUAUAAAGGGCACUAAUCCCAUUCAUGAAGAUUCUACUCUUAUGACCUAAUUACCUUCCAAAGGCCCCACCUCCUAAUACCAUCACAUUGGGGGUUAGGAUUUCAACAUACGAAUUUUGAGGGGGGGGACAGGAACAUUCAGUACAUAACAGAGGUUUAAAAAAAUAAUCAAAUGAAUUAAUAAUUCUUCUUUUUAAAAGUUACAGUGUUUAAUUUCAAUCUUAGGUUUAUUAAUAACAUUUAUUUUUCAUUAACUUGUAUUAUAAAUUACAAAAACUUUGUUGUAAUAAUUGUCAUUUAUUUAAAUGCCUAUUUAUCUCAGGUACCUUGCUAGUCACUUAAAAAAUUAUAAAAAUUUCAAGUAACGCAAAAGCAGAAAAAAUAGUGUAAUGAAGCUUCAUAAACCCAUGACCAAAUUUAAUAUUGGGAAGGUUUUAUCACUCUUAACUUCAUCAAUCCUGUGUUGCUAUUAUUGCUGCUGAAAUAAUUAAAUCUCAAAACUCAUUUUCUUCUACCUGCUGUAUACUUUAGUAUACAUUUCUAAAAUAUAAGGACAUAUUCUUAUAUAACUGCAGUGCCUCCUAACUUUUUGAAUUUGCAGCAAGGGGGUCAGCUAUCAGCAGGAUCCAGUCGUACUGGAUGAGGAUGUCUUUGAUCUGCUUCUUAGAAGCCUCAUUUACGUAUUUCUGGCAAUAGGCUACCAGGGAUUUGGAGACAUACUGCUGGAUAGCACAAAUCUGAGCCACAUGACCACUACUUUUCACAUAGACACAGAUGUCCACACCAGCAAACCACUCCUUGCCCAGAAGCAGAGGGGUCAAUAAUUUUUAAGACUAUAAAGAGGUCCUGACAUCAAGACGUUUGUGAACUGUUUACUUAAAUGAGCAUAAGAAUGGUUUUAAUUCUGAUUACAGUAGGUUUUAAGUUUACCUGUGUACAUUAAAGCACAAUCUUGUAGUUUUCUGCUUAUAGACUUGAGGAUUGACAAAAUAAAGCAGAAAUGAUGUCUUCAUGCAUUUACUAUACAGAUCAGAUCUGUUCAUUCUAUUCCAGGUAAAAAUGAAAAUGUGACUGCUCCUUUCAAAACUAGGAAUAAAGACUUCUGUUCUUUUAAGUUUUAUUACAACUGAAGUUUAAUGUAAUUCAAAAUAAAAUCAAAUAUACUUGAAUUUACACAGUUGUGAUCCUGGGGGGCUGUGUGAAAGGUACUUUCUCAAUUUAAAUGAGAACAUGAGUUCUUAUUUCUGACUCAGUGCGUAAAGAAGUACUGGUUUCCAUAUGGCUAAAUGCUUAUAAUUUGUUUUGUAAAUCUCUAGAAAUCAAAUGCAUUUAAUAUAUUUCCCUGAUUCCUCUAAGCUGAGUAAGUGACUUGUAUUUUAUCAUUGUGUUUUGAAAAAUCUGAAAACCAUCCUGUCAUUCUGUUCCAUUGGAAUAACCUAAAGCCUUUUGAUUUUAUAAUACUAUAGUCAAGCUGGUAGAUGCUGAAUAUGGAAGCUUGAUUUAAAACUCCACUUGUCCCUCAUACACCAAGAUAACUACAUUCACAGCAUAUUUUUGUUUCUCCAAAAGUACUAGUAACUAUCAACCAUCGACUGAGUAAUAUUAGAAUGUUAUAUAAUUGUCUCUAAUGGGAAUUUUACUUUCUAAAACUUCCAAUUUUAGUUUCUUUUCAUCUAAUUGAGACAUUAUUUUAAUAGGUAAAGCUUUCUAAAAUUCAAGGUGAAGUUUUAUUGUUACACAAUACAGAAACUUUUAAACAAUUAUUCAUAUAGAAGUAAAGACCUUCUUAAUACUUUUUUGGGACCAGAUCUUAUAAUUAGUGGUAGAAAAGCAUAUUGUCUUUAUGUUACUAAGGAAGCAAUAGUUAAGUGCUUAUUAUGGACUUGCAUUAUCUCAGCUACUAAGAUUUAUAGUUCUCUCCUCAUUUUCUUGUGCUAUAGCUCAAAAUUUUACUAGCAUAUUCAACAGCUAUAUUUUGUAUCUCUAUAGCUCUAUAAAAAGUGUUCAACACUUAAAAGCUUAUACAGGAGGCUUUGUUGCCCAAGAUUAGUGUCACAGCAUGGAAUAUUACUGAUUUUUAAGAAAGUGGUACAAAUUAUGGGAAAUUAUAGAUACUGUUUGUUUUAAUAACUAAGAAAAUAAACAAAUAGGCAUCCAGAGGGCACAUGGAAGACAGUAAGUAGAUUGAUGUUUAGGACUGUGUUUUAUAUAUUGGUUUAACUUAUUGGUAUUUCUAAUAAGAAUACAGAGAACAUUAAUUUCCUUAAAUCCACAGGAUGUUCUUGUUCUGUUCAAGGAGGAGAAAUGGAUGAAAGAGCCUACAGCCAGACUCCUAUCUCCUUAAUUCAAUUCAAAAAAUAUAUGAGAAUCUAUUAUUUUCACUUUGCUGAGCUGUAAUGCUACAGAUAUUGUGUUAGAAAUUGAUUCUACUCUUUAAGGAGCUUAUAGUCUGAAAGGAGCAAUAAGAUAAUGAUAUAUGUUAAUAGCUAUAAGAGAGAGAAACAAUAUAACUGAACCUUAAGAAAUAUAAAUUUAAAGCUUUCAUAGGAAACCUUGGGAGUUGGCAGGAGAGAAGGAAGACCAAAGGAGUUGGUAUUUGAGACAGGGCUUAAGGGAAGUAUGGAUAGCAUUUCAAUAGAGAGAAAAAGGGAAGGCAGAUCCUCAGGAAUACACUGGUUCAAAUAUAUCUAAUUUCCACAGAGCACAGAAAAGACAAGUCAUUUUAAAACUACCAAUUACCUUUUAACUUUACAGGUGACUGUAGCUUUGAUUUACAUCACUCUGUGGCAUUACAUGGAAAGUGGAAAAAGUGUGUUCUUUGUCACUUGCCUCUGGGUGACACUGGACAUGAAUGUGAUUUUAGAUUUAUUUCCAGUUUAAAGGACUAACUAGUAGUAUAGUGCUAAUGGUGUAGCUUAAAGACUGUCCUAUAGCAUUUGUUCUUAAUUAUUUCCACCUUUGUAGAUUUGUAUAAUUCUGGGGUCAUACAGGGUUCUAGAGCUACCUUGAAGUGGUCCUUUUGUUUUUAGAAGCUUGUCACUCCAUAGUCAAUGUAUAAAUAUAACAACUUGUUUGCACUUAGAACAAGUUCACUAUGUGUUCUAAUGAGUAAAAAUUAAGGGAUUUUGUUACUGGCCAAGCAAAAGCUUAUUUGGAAGCUCAGUUAUACUGCACUGCAAAUUAAACUCAUUAGCUGCCCUUUGCUAUGUGGAUAUACGUUUUUAAUUCUUCAUUCAUUCUUCCAAUUCUUUCAGUGCUGGAAUGAAUCCAUUCAUCUUUAAAUACUUAACUGCUUCUACUACAAUGAGUACUACUGCCAGUUUCCACUAAUAAUAGCAGUACUCAUGGCUGCCAUUUCCAGAGUACUCACUAGGUGAGCUUGUGUAGCUUUGGGCUCACAGUUAGUAAAACAAGUAAAAUUUAUGUAAUGGUUCUUACCAAAUGGCACACCAAGAUUUUUUUUUUAUGAAAGUUACUUAAUCAUAAUAUCUCAUAUUAUUUCUUAGAACUCAUUCUUUUGGAAAAGUGAAAUAGAAAAACAUACUACUAUGCAAAUGACCACUAUUACAUAAAGCUGUAAAAACUAGACCAGAAGUUUACCUCACAUGUACACCAUUCUAAGGUUGAAGUAGUCAAAGAUGAACAAGGUACUGACCGACCGCCCUACAAAGAACUGAUGAUUCAGUAGAGAGAGAGGAGGAUAAAAGAAUCAGAGUGUCUCAACCCUUGACAAGAGGACCAAGUGCCUUUAUUCCAGAGAAGGAAGUUGUCCAAGCAAACACAGUGGAUGAACGUACUAACUUUCUUGUGGAAGAAUACUCUACAUCCGGUCGUCUGGACAACAUCACACAGGUCAUGAGUUUACACACUCAGUACCUGGAGUCUUUCUUGCGGAGCCAGUUUUACAUGUUGCGCAUGGAUGGUCCCCUUCCUCUACCAUACAGGCACUAUAUUGCAAUAAUGGCUGCAGCUAGACAUCAGUGUUCUUACUUAAUAAACAUGCAUGUGGAUGAAUUUUUAAAGACUGGAGGUAUUGCUGAGUGGUUGAAUGGUUUGGAAUAUGUGCCACAAAGACUGAAAAAUCUUAAUGAAAUUAAUAAGCUGCUAGCACAUCGACCUUGGCUGAUCACAAAAGAGCACAUUCAGAAACUUGUCAAAACUGGAGAAAAUAAUUGGUCUCUGCCUGAACUGGUACAUGCUGUGGUCCUCCUGGCACAUUAUCAUGCUUUGGCAAGCUUUGUUUUUGGUAGUGGUAUCAAUCCAGAGAGAGAUCCAGAAAUCUCCAAUGGAUUCAGGCUAAUAUCAGUCAACAAUUUCUGCGUUUGUGAUCUUGCUAAUGACAACAACAUAGAGAAUGCAUCUCUUUCAGGCAGCAACUUUGGGAUUGUGGAUUCUCUAAGUGAGCUAGAGGCCUUAAUGGAAAGGAUGAAAAGACUUCAAGAAGAAAGGGAAGAUGAAGAGGCGUCUCAAGAAGAAAUGAGCACUCGUUUUGAAAAGGAGAAGAAAGAAAGUCUUUUUGUGGUCUCUGGAGAUACUUUUCAUUCAUUUCCUCAUUCAGAUUUUGAGGAUGACAUGAUUAUAACAUCUGAUGUCUCUCGAUAUAUUGAAGACCCUGGUUUUGGGUAUGAAGACUUUGCCAGACGAGGAGAAGAGCAUUUGCCAACAUUCCGAGCUCAGGACUAUACCUGGGAAAAUCAUGGGUUCUCCCUGGUGAACAGACUUUAUUCUGACAUUGGACAUCUUCUUGAUGAAAAGUUUCGGAUGGUCUACAAUCUCACAUAUAACACUAUGGCCACCCAUGAGGAUGUUGACACAACCAUGCUGCGCAGAGCUUUAUUUAACUAUGUUCACUGUAUGUUUGGAAUCAGGUAUGAUGACUAUGAUUAUGGAGAAGUUAAUCAAUUACUUGAAAGAAGCCUGAAGGUUUACAUUAAGACAGUGACCUGCUAUCCUGAGAGAACUACAAAACGCAUGUAUGAUAGUUACUGGCGGCAGUUCAAACACUCAGAAAAAGUUCAUGUCAAUCUACUUUUAAUGGAAGCACGAAUGCAAGCUGAACUUCUUUAUGCUCUUCGUGCCAUAACUCGGCAUUUGACCUGAAGUAUCACCCAAGGAAAAUGUCAUACAUGUGUAAAGACCUUUCACAUAAGAUAAACAUUGAAGCUAUUUGUGAUAUAGCAUCAAAAAUUAUUCAGUUCUCUAGUGUCAAAGUUUAGCCGUUUGUUUUUUUUUUUUUGUUUUUUGCGGCUGUAAUGUGCAAUGAUGUGUUUUAUUUUCCUUGAUGCUUAACAUUACUAACAAUUGCAAAAAUAAUACUGAGGAGCACUACUUUGCAUUGUUUGUAGUUGGAGUUUUGGAUACUGAUCAUAAAUCAUGAAUCUGGCGUAUUAAUGCUUAACUUCAGCGCCUUUGGGUUGUGUGUAUGUGUAUUUUUUCUCCCCCCACCCCGCCCUUUUUUUUUUAAGAAUAAGGACAAGUGCUUACAAUCUGCUCAAGCAAUUGUUUUUCAGAUAUUGGAAUUCAGCAAAGAGUGACCUCUCUGGCCAUUCUAAAACUUUAAUGUUGUGUCCUAAAUCUGGUGGAGGAAAAGCAUGCGCUGUUGAACCAAGCUGCUCACUGGACACAUAUUUGUGUCCCCAGGAGAUUAUUUGUCAGGCACUGUUUUUUAUUUGUUUGUUUGUUCAUUUAUUGUUGUUUUACUGCUAUUGGCGAUAACAUGAAAUGUGAUACAGCUAUUGCCCAUAAUUUAAUGUGAAAUUAAUCAUGAUGAAUUCUAUAGCAUGCUACUGAAAUGCCAAAUUCAGCUAUUUUCUUUCUCUUCUAAAAUGGAAGUUUCAGUUUUCCAUAUCAGAUGUAUAUAAGUGGAAUUAUAACACAAUCCUAUCACUGACAGUAAUCCUCAGUCACCUUAAAUAAUCAGUGCUCACAGUGCUGCUUACAGUUCAUUUAGUUGGCACAUAUAAACCUGUACCCACACAAGACUGACCAAAAAUUUUCUUUGCACAUUUUUCCUUUCUCAUAGUUUUUUUCUAUAUUUCGUUAAGCAAAGGAAGGUUAAUAUGCCUAUUUUUCCUGUUAGGCUUUUAGAAAUUAUUUUCCAUGACUUUUGUUCUUAUAAUAGGUUAGACAGUUUAUUUUUCAAAGGUAAAAAUUGUGUUUCUAUGCAUUAAUGUGAUUGAACUACAAAAACAGAGUGCAAUAUGUUCAAAAAAUACUCAACUAAACUUUCCCCCUGUCAUAUCACUGCAAAAGUGUCCUUUUAAACAGAGCCAUAAAGAAAUUUUUUUCAAAUUUCUUUAUUGCACAGGCUUUUUUCAGUUUUACCUUUCUGGGAUUGAACAAUGUUCCUUUCAUAAUGCCAAAGCAUUCCCUUCCCCAGAAAAAUCUCCUUGGACAACUGGUUUAAAAACGUUAUUAAGUCAUAGGGGAGGAAUAAGCGGCCAAAAAGUCACAUUUUUGCAUUGGUUUACGUUGCUUGAUUAGACUAUCUUCAGAGAGCACAUUAUGUGUUUAUAGCUUUAAUUUGUAUUAUGUCAAUGAACCAGUGAAGUGCCUAAAGAGAUGCUUACAACUAUCCAGUAGGACACAACUGCACUGCUUUUUAAACACUUUUUGGUUAGUUAAGGGUGACUUGAAUUGUACACAUACAUGCUAAUUUUUGAAAACUUAUCCAUUUUUCAUAGUAAAUAAUAUAGAUAAAAUUUUCUGUUAGAGUUCCCGCAAAUAUUUCAUUUUAGACUUACUUGUGAUAUAAGAUUUAACUUUUCUUUUGUGAAAGAAUCGUGAACUAGUGUUUCAUGAAAUCAUUUUCCUCUUCCAUUUAUCAUCCUCCUCUGGUACAAUAUAUUGGGUUGCUUUCUUUUAGAUUUUGUUCCAGAUAGGAAAACAAAUAUGACUGUAUACUUAUUAACAUAAGGUAGUUCUGCAUUUUUGGAUUCCAGGAUCCUGUUUGAAAUCUUCCAUGUGAGGAAAAAAUUACUAAUAUUUUUAAAGACAGGGUGGUUUAUUUAAAGAGAUUAUUCAGAGAACUUGUGCCAUAUCUCGUCUGUUUUAUUGCAUAUGCCAUAUGUUAACUUUUAUUCAAUAUUACAUUAUGUAGAUAUGUAAUACAAAGAAAAUAUUUAGGAGAAUGGCAAAACACAAAUGGCAACAUAAAUGUCCAUUUGACUUACCUAACUUCACAACUUUCAAGUUGAGGAUGUCAUUUAUUCUUGAAUUUGUUUUUUUACUAGAUGCUUUCAAUUAAUAGCCCUAUAUUUUUGUGCAGGCGAACUGUAUAACAGGAUAAAAAAUGAUUUGUAUGUAUUGAAAAGGAGGAGAAAUUCUCACAGAACACCAUAUGAGCUUUAGACCAAAAGGGGAAACAAGGUUUAAGUAACUAAAAUGGCCACUUAGUUUGUGUUUAUUUUUUUCCCUGGAAAUGUAAGUAGUUGGAGUUUAGGCUAUGGAAAUAUUAGUGCCUUUAAUAGAUCUCUUUCCUUGCAAAGUUUCUUUUUAGCUCAGCAUUGAUCUAUCUUAUCAAUAGGAAAAUAAGUUGACUUGGAACUAUAAACAAAAACAACACCAUAUAUUUAUGAACCUCAGUGAACCAGCCUAGAAAAAUUGACUUCUGCAGGUGCUAAAGCACCUACUAAUACGCAGCAUGCACAGCAUUUCAGGUUGUGAAUACCAUUUUACAACGAGUUUGCUGUUAACUCUCUUUAUCCAAUGCAAACUUGAAAUUCUGAUGCGGUUUUCCAGGGUGGUAUUUUUUCAGAGUAUUGAAUUUACUAUUUAGUAAUUUAUAGUAUAGCUUUUUAUAUUAAAAUGUGAUAUUUUUAAAAGAGAUAUCUGGUUCAAUUGGUAUAAUGACGUGAUUAUGCAAUAUGCUGAUCUACACCUUGCGCUCACAUUGUGCCAAACUUAAAUGUGCAAGUGUACGUGAGAAAAGCACAUGUGAAUGUGAAUUCUUUAAUUCUUUGCUUAUUAUGUUAAAAUUAGUCUUCAUAGUCCACUGAUGUGUAUGCUUGAAUAAUGUCUAUUUACUUUGGAAUUUCAAGAUUUCCAGCUUCAAUGGUAAUUUAUAAUUUCUCAGAUCACCUUAAGAAAUAUUGAGAUACUCUCCCACCUGAAAAUAAUCUGUUCUUUAACCCACCUGACUAUGGGAGUAGCCAGGCAGGUGCCUCACUGGCUUCUUCAGACGAGGCUUCCUCAGGUGGAUAUAUGACUAUUAGGGGAAAAGAGGCUUUUGAGACAGCUUAUUACCUCCUUCCCCUUUUUGAACUAAGUACAUUGUCUCAGUCCCAGUAUGAAUUUGUCCCAUUUGGGGUAUUUUUAAAAUAAAAGAUGGCUAACAUGGAAUCUGGGGCAUAGCCUUGGCCUUUAAUUAUGGUUGUAAGCCCAAAUAAUGGCAGAGAAACACAGGGCUGUUUUUACAACAGAAAACUCAAUAUAAGUUUUAUAUAAGAAUCCUAUAAAAUUUGAACCAGAGCUCCUAUUUAGUUGUUAUAAUGUCUCCUAAAGAUCUUAAAUGCUUCUAAAAGCUAAUUAUUAUUCCAGAGCAACUUUUUCCUUUUCCCCCUUAUAAAGUUUUUUUUUAAAUCCAAAAUCUUAGAUUUCUGUGCCACAGCAAAAUAAAAUGAUCAACAAUUAAAGAUCUGUACUUAAAAUAGUACACCAUUUUUAGUGGAGGGAGGGUGCAUGCCUAUAUGAUGGUAAGAUUCUUUUGAACUCUAAGGACAAUUCCUCAUGGAAAAAAUAAAUUUCAGUGCAUAUUAUAAAAAUGAUUUGCACUGUGUUAGCAAAAUAAGGUGUUUUAGGUUGUAUUUUAAAGACAAUUCUAAAUCAUUUCUCUGGAAAGCAAGACCUUAAAUUCUUCUCUUUAAUAGAACUGCUUUUAUGCAAAGAGAUGGUCUUAACAUGGACUAAACAGUACAUAACAAUAAUGUUUGUUAUGUAAAUAGUAUAUCACAUUUGCUUAGUAGCACAAUUCAACAGCAGGCUGAAAGUCGUGGCUCCUCUGCUCAGAUUGAGUUUUAAGUUACCUAAUUUAUGUAAUCAGAAUCUAUUCUAGGUGGCCGUCAACGUAAACUGUGUUUCCCUAUUAUAUCCCUCUGGAGACUGAGAAUCAAAUUAAAUAGUCUUUCUUCAAAGCAGUACUGUAACAUGAAUGUAUUUAUCUCAGUCAACAGAACUUAUAUGCCCACUGUAUGUGGAGCUUAUUUCAAUGCUAAUUUGGCUUAGUUAGCAGACCUAGAAUCUGCCCAGGUGAGACCUAGAACAAAAAUAGCUGGGGUGAAAUGGAUAAGAGAGGUAGAGGUAUAUGUCAAGGCAGAGCCCUAUGAGGAAGGAAGAGUUUUCAAAGAAUAUGAGGAACAUAGUGCUGAGAGUGUGGCUGCCUUCAGCACCGUACACCUAAUCUAGAGAAAAUAUUUCCCAUGUGGGAGGUCCUGUCUGCAUUCAGUCCACCCUUUUCUGCCUGCUUCUUCCUCCAAGUGCCUCAACCUCUACAUGCUCACUCUCCUCCCCUUCCCUCAGCCCAUCUUGGUCUAAGCAGCUUUCACAAUCCAAACCAAACAUCACCAGCCACCCGCUGAUAAGUCACCAGCAUUUACUUUCCUGAGUUACUUUUUCUCCAUUCAUUGAGACUAUGGAUUCAUCCCAACUCCUUCUAAAUCCCUCAACCAUCCAGCUAUAUUUUGGCUAACCUUUGCCCUAGACACUCUACCAGAUGUUAAUGCAGUAUCAAGUGUAAAUUGUGUCACCCUAUUCUGUUCUACCCUUUUCCCUGCUGCCGAAAUAUCUUGCUCUCCUCUACCUCAUCCCCAAAGAGCCUAUAAAUUCAGAGUAUCCAACCUUUUCAUGGAUUCACUCACUGUUGUUCAGUAAUACAACUUCCAUAUUUUAAAUAAAUCAUAAAAGAUUUUUGCCUUCUAUCAAAGUAGGAAACUUUAUAUUUAUACAUGAUACAGAAAUUGAACUAUUUCUAUCGUUCAGAAUUUAGCAUAUAACAGGAUUUUAAAGUGAUUGAAUUGCCAUCCUAACUUGGAUUUGUAUUAGGUUAUGAAUGAAUACUGUUGUUAGUCCAAGCUAUUUGAAUGUAAAGUUAAAAUUCUCCAGCAAUCCAGAAUGACUUGUAACCCUUCAGUGGAAUGGGAAAUUUCUGGUAUGCAAAUAGGGUGGUGUUCCAGACAUUUGUUUUAUUGGUGGUGUUUGGGCCUUGAAACACAUUUCUAAUAGAAUGACAUAUGGCAAAGGGUAUUUAGAUGGUCCUAUGGGAUCACAGAAGCCCAUAUGAUUUAAAAUAUAGAUAAAAUAACACAAAAUUGGGUACAUAAGGGUUUAACCAGGCUUUCCUGGGUUAGACUAAGCCUCUAACCUCUGUUCCUAUCCUGUUCUUAUGGGAGGAAAAAAAAUGUUCCAUGGGAUGAAAAGAAAAUGCAUUGACUUUGUAGUCUUUAUUCUCCUAGCCGCACUUCGGGUAUAUCCAGAAGGAAGAGGAAAUGCAAAGAGGAAGAAGAUGUAAUAGUUCUUCUCUCCAGCUAGGUGCACUUGAGGUUGUUCAUAAAUGUAAAAUUAUGUCAGGUUUCUAACAUGGGACACUGCACACAGUUGUCUGACCUGAUGAACCAUCCCAUUUGAAAGUAUAGAUUAUUAUUAUUUCUUGUAGUAUUUGGUUGUUUUCCAUCUCAUUCAUGAACAACUCAACCUGAUAGUAGUAUCCAAUAAAUGCCUUUCAGGGCUCAGGAAUGAAUUGACAUCCUAGUUAAGAAAUGAGACUUAAUAAUGGAGACUGAAUGAGGCGGUUUGUAUUAAAUUAUAUGCCAUGAAGUGUUCAUUUUAGCUUUAACCUAAUUAUGACUGUACCACCAUGAAGUACAGAAUGAAAAAUUAUAUAUAUGGGGGGGAAACAGAAUGAAUAUCUGAUUCUUUUGAAUGCUUGUGGAAAUCUUUGAGAUCGUGCAGGGCAUACCACAAAAUAGCCUUUAGAACAGAUACCCAAUUUUACAGUUCAUAGGACAACAUCAAACAUUAGUAAGUCUAAAUAAGAUGAAUAGAAUUUUUGUUAUGUAAAUUUUGCUAGAACAGUCUAUUUUCUUGCACCCCUCAAGUUAACCUCUUAAAAAAAUGAAUGUAUAAUUUCUACCGAAAGAAUAUCAGAGAGAAUCUCUCUGGCCUAUAGUGUUAAAAUAUUGUUCACAAAUCCUGAUUAGUUAAGUGCAUACAUUAUGAAACUUACAGAAUAAAACUUAUUAUACAUCUCUUUCUUAAAUUAAUAUCUUUACACAUUUUCAACUGGCUCCCCAAGUCUGAUAAGGAAGGAUUAAAAGAAAAAAGAAAUGUAUUAGUUGGGUGGCCAAGGAGUUUCCUUUGUAAUGUUGAGAGACUUCCGCUUUCUGAAUUUCGCUGGUUCUCUAAGGUAAAAGAGUUAAAUAGUACCCUUGUUCACCAAGGAAAGUGAUCCAAACUAUAUAUCUAGUGCAGAUAUUUCCUUUGCAUUAUUUAGUCUUCUCUGGAGAGAAAAUACAGUUUCCCCUUCCUCUUUCUCUUCACAUUUACUCUUUUCAACCCAAAAUAAGAGACAUAGAAAGCAAACCACAGCCAGUUUGGCAUCUUCUCAGUGCUACUAGUAUAGGCACAUACACAUACACAGUCUCAGCAAGGUUAUAAAGAACCCUGUCAGGUCCACUUGCAACAUGGCCUUGCUACUUGGAUUAGCUCCUUUAAGCCUGAAAAUAACUUUCCUGGUCAUGGAAGAACUGGACGCAUCUUUUAACUUAUGAAAUAGAAGUUGAACUUGAAAACUCUUUUUAAAAAAUCCUGGUUUUGCAGGACAGCUACAUAAUGAAUGUAUAUAUUAAGACUGUAGCUGAAUUGCACAUGAAAUCAGAUUGCCAACUUCUUGACUUUCAAUGUUAGACAUUUAUCCUUAAGUUGUGAGCGAUAUAUGUAGCAUGCUGUGAAAUGUCUGUUAUAGCUCUUUAAUUCAUCAGUAUUAAUACAGAAUUAUCAUUUGCGUUUCUUGGUACUUUUUAUUCAAUGUAAUCAGAAGCUGUGAUGUUUUGCCUUUGUAGUCCUGUGCUUUGUUACUGUAAUUUUUUUUUUUUUUUUACGAAGCACGUGACUGGACUAAUGUAAGGCAGAUGACGUGAUCUUUAAGACUGCUAUAUAUAUCAGUCUCUUACUCUAUAAGGUUUUAAAUUAGAAUAAGCUUUUAUCAAAUAGAUAAUUGAUGCAAUUUAGGAUUCACGCAAGUUUCAGUGUCAAAUGGCGGUCUUAUAGUUUCAAUUCUGAAAAUAGCAAACUUAAUAAACAGCCACUUUAAACUUGUUCUGGCAAACCAGACCCUGCUGUAGAUAUAGUCUAAGGUAGUUAACCAUAUAAGCCUUUUCAACUCUUAAUGCCCUCCACAUGAAUCAGCAGUUAAGAAGGUUCUAGAACCCAUGAAAGCUUUUGUAUGUAUUACUAGGUUUUGUUUUUCUUAUGUUUGCUGAUUUUACAGUUCUGACUAAAGCUGACCUAAAUGGAUCAGUUUAUGUGUAAUAUUCUAGUGCUUUAAUGACUCUUUUUUUCUUUGGAGGGAGGGUAACAUUAUUUGGACAGAUGCAGAAGGAACUGUUAGUGAGUCAAGACAAACACAUCUGAAAUAAAGGAACUGUGUAUUAACAUGUUAACAAUUCAUAACUGCACUUUUUAUGACAUUUUGAAAAUCUAUUUAUAGGUACAGAACAAUGGGUUUUGUUAAACUGUAUCACAUUUAUACUUGCAGAAAUUUAUUUCAUUGUUAUUAGUAGGAAUUUUAUUGGUUCAAUAAAAUUGGCAAAACUGAACACCAAUCAUUUGCCUACUUUGUUUAUACUGGA